GGGUCCUUCCGGCGUCGCCGGAGUGAAUUGAUCCGGGAGUUGAAGAGGGCUGCAAGGUGGGAAGUGAAGUCAGUGCCUCAGUUGCUGGUAAGGUGUAGCUGUUCUGUCCCAGUCCCCGUAGCUCUGCACCGAGCAGAAGAGGUCUAGGGUCACGCAGGGGCCAUGGCUGAGGCACUUGGGCUUGGUUCUGGCAGGCGGAGCGGACGGGGCUGAGAGCGGGGCCCUACGGGCGUAAGCGAGGUUACCCUACGCGAGUGGCGUAAAGCGGGUUUGUAAAUGCCGCCUGCCGGCUUGGGCCCGAACGCCUCCAGGAAGUCUCCUCUAGGUGGGGGCGGGAGGGGAAGGGCGAGGUUGGCCCCUGGUGCCCCGGGAGAGGGGACAGGGCGGAUGUGCCUGGGGUGGGGUCCUUUGAAGGUGUGGCUUCGGACCGAGAGGUGAGGCUGCUGUUUUCCCCCUGCUUUAGGAGCACUGGAAGAAGGAAGAGACAAAUGUUGGGGUCUACGGAUUCAGUUCCAGUUUAAUGAUGUGGCCCUCUAAGGAGAUAAUUUUGCCUUAAACAGAAAGACUUGACCCUCUUAGGUGUCAUACCUAAGCUUUCUCCUCUAAAUCUUGGUCUCUUGUUUGGAAGUGACUAACAGCAUUUUGGCAUGAGAAAGCCCUAAAAAGAUCAGUGUGUUUUUUGUGUCCAAUUCUUUUAUCACCAAAAAAGAGAAGAAAUAUUGCAGUGAAUGAAGAUUCCUCUGCAUUUUAGCACUGCUUUUUCAACUGUAGUUGGCUUUUGAAUGAGGAUGACAAUGGAAGAGAUGAAGAAUGAAGCUGAGACCACAUCCAUGGUUUCUAUGCCCCUCUAUGCAGUCAUGUAUCCUGUGUUUAAUGAGCUAGAACGAGUAAAUCUGUCUGCAGCCCAGACACUGAGAGCCGCUUUCAUCAAGGCUGAAAAAGAAAAUCCAGGUCUCACACAAGACAUCAUUAUGAAAAUUUUAGAGAAAAAAAGCGUGGAAGUUAACUUCACGGAGUCCCUUCUUCGUAUGGCAGCUGAUGAUGUAGAAGAGUAUAUGAUUGAACGACCAGAGCCAGAAUUCCAAGACCUAAACGAAAAGGCACGAGCACUUAAACAAAUUCUCAGUAAGAUCCCAGAUGAGAUCAAUGACAGAGUGAGGUUUCUGCAGACAAUCAAGGAUAUAGCUAGUGCAAUAAAAGAACUUCUUGAUACAGUGAAUAAUGUCUUCAAGAAAUAUCAAUACCAGAACCGCAGGGCACUUGAACACCAAAAGAAAGAAUUUGUAAAGUACUCCAAAAGUUUCAGUGAUACUCUGAAAACGUAUUUUAAAGAUGGCAAGGCAAUAAAUGUGUUCGUAAGUGCCAACCGACUAAUUCAUCAAACCAACUUAAUACUUCAGACCUUCAAAACUGUGGCCUGAAAGUUGUAUAUGUUAAGAGAUGUACUUCUCAGUGGCAGUAUUGAACUGCCUUUAUCUGUAAAUUUUAAAGUUUGACUGUAUAAAUUAUCAGUCCCUCCUGAAGGGAUCUAAUCCAGGAUGUUGAAUGGGAUUAUUGCCAUCUUACACCAUAUUUUUGUAAAAUGUAGCUUAAUCAUAAUCUCACACUGAAGAUUUUGCAUCACUUUUGCUAUUAUCAUUCUUUUAAGAAUUAUAAGCCAAAAGAAUUUACGCCUUAAUGUGUCAUUAUAUAACAUUCCUUAAAAGAAUUGUAAAUAUUGGUGUUUGUUUCUGACAUUUUAACUUGAAAGCGAUAUGCUGCAAGAUAAUGUAUUUAACAAUAUUUGGUGGCAAAUAUUCAAUAAAUAGUUUACAUCUGUUAAACAUUUCUUUACUUGAAAAAAUGCAUAUAUAUAUGUGUGUAUAUAUAUAUAUAUAUAUAUAUAUAUGAACAGAAGACCAAGACAACUUGGUGUAAUGUCUAAAAAACUUCUAAUGGGAGCUUAUCAGCAGUUUAUCAAAUAAUAAAGCAAGAAUUUCUAUUUUUGUCCUUAAUCACUUUGGACACAGAGUAGUCAAUGGAAAUAUUUUUGUUAAUUACUUAUAAGGUACUGAGUAUUUUUAUAUGAUUUCCAACCUGUUUUAAACGACUUAUGAGUAAGAGAUAGCAUUUUCUAGUGUUUUUGCACUAUAAUGCCACUUUUUGAACUCUUGUGACAAAUGUAGAUUUGACUCUUAAAAAUUAAGCCUUUCGUAUACUGGGCCCUCAUAAGCUUUGCACAAUUUUUUCCCAAAAAAUAGCCACAAUUAAUAGUAAUUUGAAGCUAUAUCAACGGUUGGAUUGAAAUUGUCAUGAGUGUUAAUAUUAUAUACACUCUUCAACUAGGUACAGUUUUAUUUCACCAUAGAGAAGUUUUAAGGAAAUUAUGUAUCAAGUGUUCAUGUUAAGUGGUUUCAUUUUUCAAUUAUAAAAUAAAGGGAAAAAAUCAGAA